ACAUUUAAACUGCUGCCUGCCUGUGCAGCAGCUGAGGAACCGUGGAUUUCAUAUUAUAGACUAAAACCCCAUUAAAACUGCUCAAAAUCCUUCCUGCAGCUGCCAGGCAACAACGAAAGAAGAGAGGUAAAUCCUAUUCUUUUCCAAUACAACUGAAGCACUACAUUUUAGCUCUGGCUGCUUUACAUUGCAGCUCAGUGUUAUUAGUAGAAAUAUGGAUACUGAGACGAGAACACAGCACUGCAUUGUCCAGCCAGGAAAAUAGCAGAUGUAAAAAGCUUCAAUGCAUCAACUGUCGGGAAGAGUCAACAGUGCUACAAGCAGAACGGGCAACUACAGCUCUUUUGUUUAACGAAAGAGAGAAAAUGAAAGAAAGGGAAAAUUUCAGAAGACUAGGACCCAUAUGAACAAGGAGGGUAACUCGAAGACAAGCAGACAGAUGGACACUUUGGAUACUGUGAAAAGCAAUCGCAGGAGGCAGACUGUUGGGGGAUGUGCGCAUGUUCGAUAGCAUCUUUUUUGCUGAAGUGAUGGCGUGCCAAAAGUAUUUUCAGUGGGCAUAAUCCUCUUCACAUAAAUGGCCUGACCAAGGAAGAAUGACUACAAGAGAGACAAUGUGACUGAAUUAGAAAAUGAUUGCCAAAGAAUAGUAUUAAGGAGAAGAAAACAUUUUUGGUCACCAAUCUCUCAUAUACCACUACUGGAUAUUUACAACAUGCUUCAGUGGAGGAGAAGACACUGCUGCUUUGCAAAGAUGACCUGGAAUGCCAAAAGGUCUCUGUUCCGCACUCAUCUUAUUGGAGUACUUUCUCUAGUGUUUCUUUUUGCUAUGUUUUUGUUUUUCAAUCAUCAUGACUGGCUGCCAGGCAGAGCUGGAUUCAAAGAAAACCCUGUGACAUACACUUUCCGAGGAUUUCGGUCAACAAAAAGUGAGACAAACCACAGCUCCCUUCGGAACAUUUGGAAAGAAACAGUCCCUCAAACCCUGAGGCCUCAAACAGCAACUAACUCUAAUAACACAGACCUGUCACCACAAGGAGUUACAGGCCUGGAGAAUACACUUAGUGCCAAUGGAAGUAUUUACAAUGAAAAAGGUACUGGACAUCCAAAUUCUUACCAUUUCAAAUAUAUUAUUAAUGAGCCUGAAAAAUGCCAAGAGAAAAGUCCUUUUUUAAUACUACUAAUAGCUGCAGAGCCUGGACAAAUAGAAGCUAGAAGAGCUAUUCGGCAAACUUGGGGCAAUGAAAGUCUAGCACCUGGUAUUCAAAUCACAAGAAUAUUUUUGUUGGGCUUAAGUAUUAAGCUAAAUGGCUACCUUCAACGUGCAAUACUGGAAGAAAGCAGACAAUAUCAUGAUAUAAUUCAACAGGAAUACUUAGAUACGUACUAUAAUUUGACCAUUAAAACACUAAUGGGCAUGAACUGGGUUGCAACAUACUGUCCACAUAUUCCAUAUGUUAUGAAAACUGACAGUGACAUGUUUGUCAACACUGAAUAUUUAAUCAAUAAGUUACUGAAGCCAGAUCUGCCUCCCAGACAUAACUAUUUCACUGGUUACCUAAUGCGAGGAUAUGCACCCAAUCGAAACAAAGAUAGCAAGUGGUACAUGCCACCAGACCUCUACCCAAGUGAGCGUUAUCCUGUCUUCUGUUCUGGAACUGGUUAUGUUUUUUCUGGAGAUCUGGCAGAAAAGAUUUUUAAAGUUUCUUUAGGUAUCCGCCGUUUGCACUUGGAAGAUGUAUAUGUAGGGAUCUGUCUUGCCAAGUUGAGAAUUGAUCCUGUACCCCCUCCCAAUGAGUUUGUGUUCAAUCACUGGCGAGUCUCUUAUUCGAGCUGUAAAUACAGCCACCUAAUUACCUCUCAUCAGUUCCAGCCUAGUGAACUGAUAAAAUACUGGAACCAUUUACAACAAAAUAAGCACAAUGCCUGUGCCAACGCAGCAAAAGAAAAGGCAGGCAGGUAUCGCCACCGUAAACUACAUUAGAAAAGACAAUUUUUUUUCAAAUGUGCAAUUUGUAAAUAUUGCUAAAAGCAUGUAUAGUUAGAACUGAUUACAUCCGUAGGACAAGUUUUAGUUAAAACUCAUCACAUAAAGAAAUUCAAGAAGUAUUUUUUUAAUUUCUGAAGAAGUUAAUUCUUAAAACUAUAACAUUAUAUAACAAAAAAGGUUUCCCAAAACAAUCUAUUUAAAAAACUGUAUAAGGAGAUUCUGUGUAUUAACAUGCAAUAACAAGCAUGCAUAAAUCAAUGGUUCAAGUCUUCUGUUAGGGGCCAAUAAAAUGUAUCUGCAUAUGUUUUCCACAUAAAUUUUAAUUCAAGAAAUGACAGUCAAAAGAUCCUUCAUUUUAGAUUAAGCUUUUCAUUUUAAUAUAUAAUUUAAUGUAAAUAAAACAUCACUAUCAAUUUUAAGGAAACUUUUUAAUUGUGCAAAGGAUAAAUUUUUUGACCUAUUUUAGGGUUCUAAAUGCAAUAAGAUUUAGUUGAGUUAUUCCACAAACACAUUAUAAAGUUCAGAUGUUUCAUCAAUGCAGUUCUCACGAAAGUAUUUACUUUUUAAAAAUAACUGAGAUAUUAUUUUAAAUUUCUUUUAUUAAUACUUUCUUUUAUUAAUAUAUGGGGGAAAAUUAUUUUGACAUGACGUGGUAAAAUGUGAAAAACUAAUGUGUCUCAGGCUCAAGUUUUUAUAGUUAUUAAAUGUUUCAAAAUAGACAAGUUUUGUUUCCUCAUUGAUGUUAAGAACCAAACUCCUAUUUCAAUGAGUUAUUGGAUUAGACCAAUUACUGCACUCUUAAACAGCACCACCAUUUAAUUUCAUGUAUAUCUAACUUCGAAUAUAUCUGUAAAGAUAAUCGAAGCAAAAGUAAUCACUUAAAGGCACAAAUAGGAUGUACUGUUGAAAAAGAUAAAGAGUGCAGGUGCAGUUUCAUUCAACACAUUUUUAAGAUGCAUGUCUGCCAAAAUGCAACAUACGGGAAGUUUAUUUCCUGACAGCAGGUGUACACAUGCCAACACUUAAUCAUUUUAUGGCACCUAUUUCUUUCUUGGAGUGCCAAGUUUGCAAACCUGCAGUUUUUAAUUUGGUAGAUGACAAAUAUUCUGAAUCACCAAUUAAAAACCUUUUUGGGAGGGAUGGGGAAAACUACAAACGUUUGACAAACACAAUUCUAGGAUGAACAAUGUAUACAAUGCACUUUUAUGAAGUUUUUAAAAAUAAAGGAAAACAAAAAACUUUACUGAGUGUUAUAAGUAUUUUCACAAUAAUUUUGUUUGACUCCAUCAUGAAUUUUAAAAUCAAGAAAUACCAACCUACUAACUAAAAUAGUGUUUUUAUUCCAUACAAGUAUGUAAAUCUGUCAAUCUUAAUUUAGUCAGAAUGUUUCUUAAUUCUAAUAACAAUCAUUUUUACCUCUUAUUCUAUUAUUAAGGGAUAAAUCACCAGAAGAGAAUUGUAACAUUUGUGAAACUUGAAAACACUAAAACUGUUUAAGUGCUUAUCUCCAUUUCAAAUCAGUAGCCUAAGUGUUCUACUCUAAAUCAAGUGAUUCUGA